CUCUCCCCUUGCGGCCUUUCUAACGUUGGCCCUGCUCUUGUGGCCUCCCGCAGAAUGUGGAUGACGCCCAAAAGAAGCAAGAUGGAAGUCGACGAGGCUCUAGUUUUCCGGCCCGAGUGGACCCAGCGUUAUUUGGUGGUGGAGCCUCCGGAGGGCGAUGGGGCCCUGUGCCUGGUCUGUCGCCGCCUCAUCGUAGCUACCCGCGAACGCGACGUCAGGCGCCACUACGAGGCUGAGCACGAAUACUACGAGCGGUAUGUGGCGGACGGCGAGCGCGCGGCCCUGGUGGAGCGUCUGCGUCAGGGCGACUUGCCCGUGGCCUCCUUCACUCCUGAAGAGAGAGCUGCUCGUGCAGGCCUCGGGCUCUGCCGCCUCUUGGCCUUGAAGGGUCGCGGCUGGGGUGAGGGGGACUUUGUAUACCAGUGCAUGGAGGUGUUGCUGAGAGAGGUACUGCCCGAGCAUGUAAGCGUCCUGCAAGGCGUUGACUUAUCUCCAGAUAUCACAAGGCAGAGGAUCCUGAGCAUUGACAGGAAUCUACGCAACCAGCUUUUUAACCGAGCCAGGGACUUUAAAGCCUAUUCUCUUGCCUUGGACGACCAGGCUUUUGUGGCCUAUGAGAACUACCUCCUGGUCUUUAUCCGCGGUGUAGGCCCUGAGUUGGAGGUGCAAGAAGAUCUUCUGACCAUAAUCAACCUGACUCAUCAUUUCAGUGUUGGUGCGCUCAUGUCGGCAAUCCUAGAGUCCCUGCAGACAGCAGGGCUUAGCUUGCAGAGAAUGGUUGGACUGACCACGACCCAUACUUUGAGGAUGAUUGGUGAGAACUCAGGACUCGUCUCAUACAUGAGAGAAAAGGCCGUAAGCCCCAACUGUUGGAAUGUCAUUCAUUAUUCAGGAUUUCUUCACUUGGAACUGUUGAGCUCCUAUGAUGUAGAUGUUAAUCAGAUCAUAAAUACCAUAUCCGAAUGGAUAGUUUUGAUUAAGACCAGAGGCGUUAGGCGACCUGAAUUUCAGACUUUACUAACGGAAUCUGAAUCAGAGCAUGGUGAAAGGGUUAAUGGACGAUGUCUGAACAAUUGGCUUAGGAGAGGGAAAACUUUAAAACUAAUAUUCUCUCUAAGAAAAGAAAUGGAAGCGUUCUUGGUUUCAGUAGGGGCAACAACAGUCCACUUCUCAGACAAACAAUGGCUUUGUGACUUUGGCUUCUUGGUGGACAUUAUGGAACACCUUCGAGAACUCAGUGAAGAAUUACGAGUUAGUAAAGUCUUUGCUGCUGCUGCCUUUGACCAUAUUUGUACUUUCGAAGUUAAGCUGAAUUUAUUUCAAAGACAUAUUGAGGAAAAAAAUCUAACAGACUUUCCUGCCCUCAGAGAAGUUGUUGAUGAGCUAAAACAGCAAAAUAAGGAAGAUGAAAAAAUAUUUGAUCCUGAUAGGUAUCAAAUGGUGAUCUGUCGUCUCCAAAAAGAAUUUGAGAGACAUUUUAAGGACCUCAGGUUCAUUAAAAAGGACUUAGAACUUUUUUCAAAUCCAUUUAACUUUAAACCUGAAUAUGCACCUAUUUCAGUGAGGGUGGAGCUAACAAAACUUCAGGCAAACACUAAUCUUUGGAAUGAAUACAGAAUCAAAGACUUGGGGCAGUUUUAUGCUGGAUUGUCUGCUGAAUCCUACCCAAUUAUCAAAGGGGUUGCCUGUAAGGUGGCAUCCUUGUUUGAUAGUAACCAAAUCUGUGAAAAGGCUUUUUCAUAUUUGACUCGAAACCAACACACUUUGAGUCAGCCAUUAACAGAUGAGCAUCUCCAAGCCCUGUUUCGGGUUGCCACAACUGAAAUGGAGCCCGGUUGGGAUGACCUUGUGAGAGAAAGAAAUGAAUCUAAUCCAUAAGGCUUUGUAGUACAAGAUUGAAAAACUCAACAAGAAUUUAAUUCUAAAAGCAAAAAUUGGUUUGAGUUUUCAAGUUUACUAAUUUGGAUUGUGAGAAAGUACCAAGUACCAGCCGUCCAAACUGAUCACAAUUAAAAUUCUGACAGUUGCCUUUUUUUUCAUCUCAAAUGGCAGCAUGGGACUGAAACAUGAGAAUGCCACCUUUUUUAAAACUUAGUUUAGUGACAAAGUCAUUGUCUUUUAUGAUAUAGUUAAUUUUAAAGAGAUUUAGUAUUAAUGUGAGUUGAAUUUGCAGUCUGUUUUUUAGGUGUUCUGAAGAUAAAUGCCAAAAAUUUCAGCUCUUAUUUUAAUGGAGUGUUAAAAUUCUGAUUCAUAUAGUCUUAAAUUAUCAACUCCUUAAAUGUGCUUUUGAACCAAUUUGCAGAAGCUCACAUAGCAAGUUCAUAAGUUUCCAAAAAGGAAGCCCAUACAUAACAGUGGAGGUGUUUUGUCUAACCAUCAAAAUGUUUGAGACUUUUUUUUAAACAUUUCUGAGUUCGAAGGUAAUACUGACAGAUUUCUUCCCUCUUCCCUCCCCAUCACCCACCUCAGUGAUAACACAUUACUGAUAGAGGAAGUCAUUAGAAUCAUUUUUAAGUUUCAGAUAUAGGAGACUUCAUGCAAUUUGGAGAUAAGACUAAUUAUUGGGGGUUUUCCUUGGAUUUUUUUUUUAAUAACUGGGGGCUAUUUUAUCAGCUUGCCUAUUAAAGGACUAUGGUAAGUAUAGAAUCUUAAUGGUUGCCAGUUAGUAAUUCUUUUUUUUUUUUUUUUUACUGUAGACACAAGUUUGGCCCUAUCAAAAACGAUGAGGAAAAAAGAUUGCACUCCAGGAUUAGGAGGUGUGAGAUAUUUUAGCUUUUUUGUCUUAUCUGCGUGGGUAUUGCUGCUUUAUUUUAAAAAAUCCUGCCUAAAGUAAACACUUUGUUUUAAAAUGAUACAGUAUCAGAUUUUGUUAGAUGCUAGAAAUGGAUUUAUUCUAAAAUUUGGAACUGUCGUACACAUUCUAUAUGUAAGAUAGCACACAAGUAGAAAUAUUUAAAAGCAGUCUUAUUCACAGAUUGCAGUAAUUCUGUAUUUCUACUAAGAUAAUCUGCUUUGUGCCAAAACAGUAAUUUCCAAACUUCUGUUCACCAUGAAAAGGCAAUCUUAAAGUUCAUUAUGUAAAACUAAUUAUAAACAGGACCCAAUUUAUAUUCAUAGAUCCUCUCAAGUAUUAUACAAUUUAAAAACUCUUGUUCCAAAGUCCUGUCUUAACUAUUGAAACACCUUAAUCUGUGGUUACUAAUCCAGCAAAUUCAAGGAACCAGGCUAUGACUAAGAAUUUAGGUGGAAUUGAUGUCUGGGCAAUUAAAAUAAAUGGCAUAAGAGCUUAAAAACCAAAGUUGUGCCAGUGGCUUUCAACUAGAGGCAGUAACCUGUCAUUCCAGAGGAUGCUGAGAAAUGUGUAGGGGCACUUUUUUGGUUGUCAUAUUUACUAGGGGCUUCUGUUGGCAUUUAAGCCUAAAGACACUCACCCCUGCAGUGCAUGGGACAGCCUGGCACAAUGAAGAAUUAGCCCUCCCAAAAUGUAGAUUAUUUUAUUUCAAGGGAUAGGGCAGAUUACCAUUAGAAGCAAAAUUAAAAGUACAAGCUGGGCAAACUGACAGAAUACUAGAUAGGAGAGACUAAUUCCAACCUUCUAAAUUUGGCUAGUAAAGUGCAAUAAAGGCAUUGAUAAGUUCUGUUAGCUCACCAUAGCACUUGUAAAUCAGGAAUUAAUAAUUGAAUCAGAUUUAAGGGCUCUGUCCUGUUAUACAUAUUUAAGGCAGAAAAAAAGUUACAUGUCGAUUAGGUACUUAUCAAGAAUGGUCAAGCUGAGAUUUUGGUUAAUAGAGUAAGCUUACAUAUCUAGAGAAACAACAUAGUGGAAAACCGAAAAAAAAAAACAGAAAAAUCUACCGGUAAUUUCCCAAUAGCUUUGAAUAUUCACAGCAGAGCUUUAUUACUUGAGAGAAAGACUGGAAGACCUGAAAGCCACUUCUGCUUUCUAACCCCAGUUCCUUAAAUAUUGAAAUCUUGUACAUUUUGUGAAAUUCCAGUAUGUUUUGCUUAAGGUGUUAAUAAAAUUAGUUUGCAUCAUGUAGUCAUUGAGUGAGGGGGAGAUAUAAGCCAAGGAUUUUAAAUUGACCCUUAGCUAUAGAGAAUUUGCUAUAAGCUAGUCUUGUUUGUAAAAAAAAAAAAAAAAAAAGAAAAAGAAAAAAGUGUAUUUUACUGUUUUCUGUAUUAAGUAAUUCUGUAACUGCAUGGCAGUCUUUUUUUUUUUAAAUAAAUAUAGUUGUUACUGGUCCUGUUGUAGCAGUGAAUAUAGUUAAAAUACGUACAUUAAAAAAAAAAUUAUUAGGUCCUUACCAGUUACUGUCCUAUAGCUCAUUCCUACUAGUUUUCUUGACAGAUUUGUAUUCCCAGUGUCCCGUAUUGCCACUCAAAUUGCUCUACUAUGCUAAGUCCUUGUUAAUAGUCUUACCCUCCUUGAAACACUUGAACACUUGAUGACUUUAGCUUUGAGGAGAUACCAUCUCCAGGUGUGCUUUCUUAGUCUUUGCAGGCACCUCUUCCCUUCAAUAUCUGUUCUUCGUAUUUUUAAAAAAAUUUGUUUUAGACUGCCUUGUUCUGUGUCAGCUCGCUAGCUGAUCUCAUUUCCUUCCAUGGUUUCCUUACCAUUUAUAUGCAAAUGACUGUCAGAUUCAUAUCUCCUUUCUAGAUCUUCCCUAAUUGAUGUAUCUAAUUGCUAACAAAUGCUCUUUGCUGUCUCAGGCACUACAUGUCAUUGAUCUUGCCCCCAAUCCUGCUCCUCCUCUCAUGUUUCCUCUUUGACUAAAUGGCAUUACCACUACCAACCAUUCAUUUGUCCUUUUUACCAAUUCUCCAAUGCUGCCAUUUUAAUUCAGGCCAUCAACCUACCUAAAUUAUAGCAACAGCCUCCUUAUUAGUCUCCCUGUUUUUUAUUUUUAUUCCUUUCUACACUACAACCAAAUUGCUCCAAAAGACUUACUGAUCAUGUCACUGCAUUGCUUUCACCAUUGCUCUUAGGGUACAAUACAAAUUUAUCUUCAUCUUUAAGGUCUCAGUAUGCCACUUCAUCUAGGAAACCUUCAUUGAUGCCCUCUAGAUUAGGUGCCCUUACUAUCCAUUCCCUAUACACCCUGUUCUUUCCCAGACAUACACUUGGCACACUUUAUUGUUACUGCUUAUUGAUCACUGCUAGACUGUAAGCUUUGUAAGGGCAGGGACCAUAUAAGCCUUGUUCACUGUUAUAUCUCUAGUGCUUAGCACAAUGCCUGGCAUUUCAAUAAAUGUUUGGACAAACGAAUAUUUGUGUAGUGUUUUACAAUUUUUGAAGCUCUUUCACAGUCUUAUUUGACCUUCACAGUCAUUCUGCCUUAGACUGUCCAUUGGGUAACUUUUAUCCACAUAUUACUAAUUGAAAAAUGAAGACAAGUUCUUUGUAACUAGGGACCUCGUUGUAUUCUCAGAAUUUAGUGUAGUGCUUAGCAUGUGACUUAAAUAUGUAUUAUGUGACUGUUAAACAAAUUGUGGUUUUCUCUGUUGUAUGAAAGGAGAGAAGGAUAACAAAUUGCGGUUUUCCCUGGUAAACACAGUAAGUAGUAAACUCAGGAUUCAAAACCAAAUAUACACACCAAAUCCACUAUGUAAUAUUAAGUUUGCAUAUCCAUGUAUAGAAUCUUAUUUUUUUUUACCCUUUGUAAACAGUGUCAUAUAUAUAUAUAUAUUUUUUUUUUUUUUUUAAAUUUCCAAAGGAACCUACAUAUAGAGGGAAAAGAUUAGACAACUACUUAGUGAACUAAAACAAUAUGUUUUUACUAAAUGUUACAUUUAGUAUUGGAAAAAGAUAAUGCCGCCUAAGAGUUAAUAAUCAUUUUUCCUUUUGUAGGCAUCAACACUAGGAGAAAAUGGCAUGCUAUUUACUUGCUACUUUCCUUUACAGAUGAUUUUUGGCUCUUCUGGGAUUUAAAAGUAAGUAAAUUUAACAAAGUAGAAGACUGACUCAGCCCUUCUGGUCACUAUAUAUUCAGUUCACUUGUUUUUACACCUGCAGAAUGUCCUUAUCACCCAAAGGGAGAUGACCCAAAAGUGACAUCUAGUUAAUGUAUACUUCUAAAGUUUGCUGUAUUCCUUUGCCUUCUUGUUCCCAUGCCUCUCUGAACUUAAUUUCUGGGUAACUGAGGCUUUUCAGGCUUAGGUGGGAAAGCCACACCCUUAGUCUGUUUCCUUAAGCCAUUUUGACCAAUUUAUGGGAUUAACUAGUAUAAUCUUAGUUGGAGUUUUAGUCUGAGGCAUAUUAAGUCAUUCAGAGAUCUUAACAGUAGGUGUCAUAGUCAUCCAGUGAUUUGGUGCUUGCUGCAAAACUGGCUUUUUUUUUUUUUUUUUUUUUUGAGGCGGGGUCUCACUUUGUCACCCAGGCUGGAGUGCAGAGGUACAAUCUCAGCUCAAUGCAAUCUCUGCCUUCCUGGCUCAAGCAAUUCUCCCACUGCAGCCUCCUAAGUAGCUGGGAAUACAGGUAUACACGAGUACACCCAGCUAAUUUUUGUAUUUUUAUGUGGAGACAGGGUCUUGCUGUAUUCCCCAGGCUAGUCUCGAAUUCCUGGACUCAAGCAGUCCGCCCGCCUCGGGCUCCCAAAAUGUUGGUGUUAUACGUGUGAGCCUCUGCACCCGGCGGCAAAACUGGCUUUUAAUCAACCUUUUGGCUAAAGGAUUUCUCUUUUUAUUUAUUUGUAAAAGGAUUUCCCAUUUUUAUCUUUCUUUUUGAUAUUAAAAUGUUGCCUCAUCCUACCCAGUAAGUACUUGAAUUUGAAUUCUCUUCCUUUUCAUUUUUGCCUGCAAACUGACCAGUCUUUUCUGAGUUCAUCUCUUCUGUACGUUUUGUCAAGUGCAGUGAACAGCAACUACAAAAUAUUUUGUUUUUCUGUCUUUUUCUUUAGUAAAGGGUAGAUGAUCUGCCUUUCAGGUUAUCUCAAGGGGCAGUUUCACCUUUCCAUAAUAUAAAUUACCCUUGUGUAAGUUAUUUCUUCCAUCUUCUGAUAGCAAUUUCCUGAAUGCCUGCCAGCUAACCAUUAAGCCAGUGUUCAGUAUUUUAGCAUUUUAAAAAACAAGGGACCAAUUUCUGUGUCAGCAUGGGCUAGCUUGCCAUUGAAUAACAAAGGCAAAAUCUCACUGUCUCACACAACUUUUCUAUUGCAACUUGCCUAGGGACUUUGGUUUAGAUCAUAGGUUGGCCAUGAUCAAACUAUGGUCCAUGGGCAAAAUCUGUCUAGCUCCUUAUUUAUCUAAAUAAAGUUUUACUGGAAUAUAGCCUUGUCCAUUUAUUUAUUAUCUGUGGCUACUUUGGUUCUACAAUGGCACAGCUGAGUAGUUGCUACAGAGUGUGUACAUCUCACAAAACCUAAAAUACUUAUUCUGUGGCCCUUUACAGAGAAAGUUCACCAAUUUGUGCUCUAAGUUGCCUUCAUUCUGGGUCUCAGGCUGACAAAGCAGAUACCAUCAGGAGUGUGGGUGCUAACUUUGGGAAAUGAAAAAAGAGUAUGGCAAAUCACUUAAGGACUCUUAAAGGACUUUCAUUGGCCAAAGCAAAUCACAUAGCCACAUUAAAGUUCUAGGAGGAGUGUGAUCCUUGCAUAUACCUGGGAGAAAAACCAGAAAUAUUUGGAAGACAACACCACUGAUUAACAUCUUCAUUUAUAUGCUUUCUUCCAAUAUAUUUUCAACUUGUUACUGAGGUAAAAUUUAAAAGUGUACCGAUAUUAAGUGUACACCUCAGUGGGUUUUUAUAUAUGCCCUUGAAUGCACCACCCAGGUCAAAAUAUAGAAUAUUUCUAGCACUUCAGUAGGUGUCCUUAUGUUCCCCAGGCCCCCACCAACCCCUUUUAUCACCACGGAUUAGUUUUGCCUGUUUUAAAACUUUAUGUAAGUGAAAUAAUUAUAUGCACUCUUCCGUGUCUUGUUCAACAUUGUAUCUGUGAGAGUAAUCCAUGUUAUAUGUAGUAGCAGUUCAUGUUUUACUUCUGUGUAGUAUUCCAUUGUGUGACUACAUCACAACUUACCCAUUCUACCGUUGAUAGAAAUUUAGGUUGUUUCCAGCUUGUGGUCAUUAUGAAUAAAGUUACUAUGAAAAUGA